AGAGCAGCCCGGAGACCGCUGCCGCCGCUGCCGCUGCUACCACCGCUGCCACCUGAGGAGACCCGCCGCCCCCCCGUCGCCGCCUCCUGCGAGUCCUUCUUAGCACCUGGCGUUUCAUGCACAUUGCCACUGCCAUUAUUAUUAUCAUUCCAAUACAAGGAAAAUAAAAGAAGAUACCAGCGAAAAGAACCGCUUACACCUUUCCGAAUUACUCAAGUGUCUCCUGGAAACAGAGGGUCGUUGUCCCCGGAGGAGCAGCCGAAGGGCCCGUGGGCUGGUGUUGACCGGGAGGGAGGAGGAGUUGGGGGCAUUGCGUGGUGGAAAGUUGCGUGCGGCAGAGAACCGAAGGUGCAGCGCCACAGCCCAGGGGACGGUGUGUCUGGGAGAAGACGCUGCCCCUGCGUCGGGACCCGCCAGCGCGCGGGCACCGCGGGGCCCGGGACGACGCCCCCUCCUGCGGCGUGGACUCCGUCAGUGGCCCACCAAGAAGGAGGAGGAAUAUGGAAUCCAAGGGGGCCAGUUCCUGCCGUCUGCUCUUCUGCCUCUUGAUCUCCGCCACCGUCUUCAGGCCAGGCCUUGGAUGGUAUACUGUAAAUUCAGCAUAUGGAGAUACCAUUAUCAUACCUUGCCGACUUGACGUACCUCAGAAUCUCAUGUUUGGCAAAUGGAAAUAUGAAAAGCCCGAUGGCUCCCCAGUAUUUAUUGCCUUCAGAUCCUCUACAAAGAAAAGUGUGCAGUACGACGAUGUACCAGAAUACAAAGACAGAUUGAACCUCUCAGAAAACUACACUUUGUCUAUCAGUAAUGCAAGGAUCAGUGAUGAAAAGAGAUUUGUGUGCAUGCUAGUAACUGAGGACAACGUGUUUGAGGCACCUACAAUAGUCAAGGUGUUCAAGCAACCAUCUAAACCUGAAAUUGUAAGCAAAGCACUGUUUCUCGAAACAGAGCAGCUAAAAAAGUUGGGUGACUGCAUUUCAGAAGACAGUUAUCCAGAUGGCAAUAUCACAUGGUACAGGAAUGGAAAAGUGCUACAUCCCCUUGAAGGAGCGGUGGUCAUAAUUUUUAAAAAGGAAAUGGACCCAGUGACUCAGCUCUAUACCAUGACUUCCACCCUGGAGUACAAGACAACCAAGGCUGACAUACAAAUGCCAUUCACCUGCUCGGUGACAUAUUAUGGACCAUCUGGCCAGAAAACAAUUCAUUCUGAACAGGCAGUAUUUGAUAUUUACUAUCCUACAGAGCAGGUGACAAUACAAGUGCUGCCACCAAAAAAUGCCAUCAAAGAAGGGGAUAACAUCACUCUUAAAUGCUUAGGGAAUGGCAACCCUCCCCCAGAGGAAUUUUUGUUUUACUUACCAGGACAGCCCGAAGGAAUAAGAAGCUCAAAUACUUACACACUGACGGAUGUGAGGCGCAAUGCAACAGGAGACUACAAGUGUUCCCUGAUAGACAAAAAAAGCAUGAUUGCUUCAACAGCUAUCACAGUUCACUAUUUGGAUUUGUCCUUAAACCCAAGUGGAGAAGUGACUAGACAGAUUGGUGAUGCCCUACCCGUGUCAUGCACAAUAUCUGCUAGCAGGAAUGCAACUGUGGUAUGGAUGAAAGAUAACAUCAGGCUUCGAUCUAGCCCGUCAUUUUCUAGUCUUCAUUAUCAGGAUGCUGGAAACUAUGUCUGCGAAACUGCUCUGCAGGAGGUUGAAGGACUAAAGAAAAGAGAGUCAUUGACUCUCAUUGUAGAAGGCAAACCUCAAAUAAAAAUGACAAAGAAAACUGAUCCCAGUGGACUAUCUAAAACAAUAAUCUGCCAUGUGGAAGGUUUUCCAAAGCCAGCCAUUCAAUGGACAAUUACUGGCAGUGGAAGCGUCAUAAACCAAACAGAGGAAUCUCCUUAUAUUAAUGGCAGGUAUUAUAGUAAAAUUAUCAUUUCCCCUGAAGAGAAUGUUACAUUAACUUGCACAGCAGAAAACCAACUGGAGAGAACAGUAAACUCCUUGAAUGUCUCUGCUAUAAGUAUUCCAGAACACGAUGAGGCAGACGAGAUAAGUGAUGAAAACAGAGAAAAGGUGAAUGACCAGGCAAAACUAAUUGUGGGAAUCGUUGUUGGUCUCCUCCUUGCUGCCCUUGUUGCUGGUGUCGUCUACUGGCUGUACAUGAAGAAGUCAAAGACUGCAUCAAAACAUGUAAACAAGGACCUCGGUAAUAUGGAAGAAAACAAAAAGUUAGAAGAAAACAAUCACAAAACUGAAGCCUAAGAGAGAAACUGUCCUAGUUGUCCAGAGAUAAAAAUCAUAUAGACCAAUUGAAGCAUGAACGUGGAUUGUAUUUAAGACAUAAACAAAGACAUUGACAGCAAUUCAUGGUUCAAGUAUUAAGCAGUUCAUUCUACCAAGCUGUCACAGGUUUUCAGAGAAUUAUCUCAAGUAAAACAAAUGAAAUUUAAUUACAAACAAUAAGAACAAGUUUUGGCAGCCAUGAUAAUAGGUCAUAUGUUGUGUUUGGUUCAAUUUUUUUUCCGUAAAUGUCUGCACUGAGGAUUUCUUUUUGGUUUGCCUUUUAUGUAAAUUUUUUACGUAGCUAUUUUUAUACACUGUAAGCUUUGUUCUGGGAGUUGCUGUUAAUCUGAUGUAUAAUGUAAUGUUUUUAUUUCAAUUGUUUAUAUGGAUAAUCUGAGCAGGUACAUUUCUGAUUCUGAUUGCUAUCAGCAAUGCCCCAAACUUUCUCAUAAGCACCUAAAACCCAAAGGUGGCAGCUUGUGAAGAUUGGGGACACUCAUAUUGCCCUAAUUAAAAACUGUGAUUUUUAUCACAAGGGAGGGGAGGCCGAGAGUCAGACUGAUAGACACCAUAGGAGCCGACUCUUUGAUAUGCCACCAGCGAACUCUCAGAAAUAAAUCACAGAUGCAUAUAGACACACAUACAUAAUGGUACUCCCAAACUGACAAUUUUACCUAUUCUGAAAAAGACAUAAAACAGAAUUUGGUAGCACUUACCUCUACAGACACCUGCUAAUAAAUUAUUUUCUGUCAAAAGAAAAAACACAAGCAUGUGUGAGAGACAGUUUGGAAAAAUCAUGGUCAACAUUCCCAUUUUCAUAGAUCACAAUGUAAAUCACUAUAAUUACAAAUUGGUGUUAAAUCCUUUGGGUUAUCCACUGCCUUAAAAUUAUACCUAUUUCAUGUUUAAAAAGAUAUCAAUCAGAAUUGGAGUUUUUAACAGUGGUCAUUAUCAAAGCUGUGUUAUUUUCCACAGAAUAUAGAAUAUAUAUUUUUUUCGUGUGUGUUUUUGUUAACUACCCUACAGAUAUUGAAUGCACCUUGAGAUAAUUUAGUGUUUUUAACUGAUACAUAAUUUAUCAAGCAGUACAUGAAAGUGUAAUAAUAAAAUGUCUAUGUAUCUUUAGUUACAUUCAAAUUUGUAACUUUAUAAACAUGUUUUAUGCUUGAGGAAAUUUUUAAGGUGGUAGUAUAAAUGGAAACUUUUUGAAGUAGACCAGAUAUGGGCUACUUGUGACUAGACUUUUAAACUUUGCUCUUUCAAGCAGAAGCCUGGUUUCUGGGAGAACACUGCACAGCGAUUUCUUUCCCAGGAUUUACACAACUUUAAAGGGAAGAUAAAUGAACAUCAGAUUUCUAGGUAUAGAACUAUGUUAUUGAAAGGAAAAGGAAAACUGGUGUUUGUUUCUUAGACUCAUGAAAUAAAAAAUUAUGAAGGCAAUGAAAAAUAAAUUGAAAAUUAAAGUCAGAUGAGAAUAGGAAUAAUACUUUGCCACUUCUGCAUUAUUUAGAAACAUACGUUAUUGUACAUUUGUAAACCAUUUACUGUCUGGGCAAUAGUGACUCCGUUUAAUAAAAGCUUCCGUAGUGCAUUGGUAUGGAUUAAAUGCAUAAAAUAUUCUUAGACUCGAUGCUGUAUAAAAUAUUAUGGGAAAAAAAGAAAAUACGUUAUUUUGCCUCUAAACUUUUAUUGAAGUUUUAUUUGGCAGGAAAAAAAAUUGAAUCUUGGUCAACAUUUAAACCAAAGUAAAAGGGGAAAAACCAAAGUUAUUUGUUUUGCAUGGCUAAGCCAUUCUGUUAUCUCUGUAAAUACUGUGAUUUCUUUUUUAUUUUCUCUUUAGAAUUUUGUUAAAGAAAUUCUAAAAUUUUUAAACACCUGCUCUCCACAAUAAAUCACAAACACUAAAAUAAAAUUACUUCCAUAUAAAUAUUAUUUUCUCUUUUGGUGUGGGAGAUCAAAGGUUUAAAGUCUAACUUCUAAGAUAUAUUUGCAGAAAGAAGCAACAUGACAAUAGAGAGAGUUAUGCUACAAUUAUUUCUUGGUUUCCACUUGCAAUGGUUAAUUAAGUCCAAAAACAGCUGUCAGAACCUCGAGAGCAGAACAUGAGAAACUCAGAGCUCUGGACCGAAAGCAGAAAGUUUGCCGGGAAAAAAAAAGACAACAUUAUUACCAUCGAUUCAGUGCCUGGAUAAAGAGGAAAGCUUACUUGUUUAAUGGCAGCCACAUGCACGAAGAUGCUAAGAAGAAAAAGAAUUCCAAAUCCUCAACUUUUGAGGUUUCGGCUCUCCAAUUUAACUCUUUGGCAACAGGAAACAGGUUUUGCAAGUUCAAGGUUCACUCCCUAUAUGUGAUUAUAGGAAUUGUUUGUGGAAAUGGAUUAACAUACCCGUCUAUGCCUAAAAGAUAAUAAAACUGAAAUAUGUCUUCA